GAGCCGAUCGUGCCACCAUAGCUCCUGCUGCUGCCUCUACCGCUGCGGCUACCGCGGCGGAGCUGAAAUUGCCGAACGCGAUGCCCGAGGGCGCUGUGAGCGGGGUGGCCUUAGCUCGCCGAGGCUGGUCAGUGAGAGGGCAUACUGGGAAGCCCUCUGGAGUGGGAAGACAGUGCCGCUGUUGAGACAAGACCCAGGACUGGGCCGGGGACUGUCCCAAAGGGUUUCUCGUCAUAAUGGCUGUGGAAGGGUCAACCAUUACCAGCCGGAUCAAGAAUCUGUUGAGAUCUCCAUCCAUCAAACUGCGCAGGAGUAAGGCAGGAAACCGACGAGAGGACCUCAGCUCCAAGGUGACCUUGGAGAAGGUGCUGGGAAUUACAGUGUCUGGAGGCAGAGGACUUGCCUGUGACCCCCGAUCAGGUUUAGUUGCUUACCCAGCAGGGUGUGUGGUUGUGUUGUUCAAUCCCCGGAAACACAAACAGCACCACAUCCUCAACAGUUCCAGGAAAACCAUCACUGCCCUUGCCUUCUCCCCUGAUGGCAAGUACUUGGUCACUGGAGAGAGUGGGCACAUGCCUGCCGUGCGGGUUUGGGACGUGGCAGAGCACAGCCAGGUGGCCGAGCUGCAGGAGCACAAGUAUGGUGUGGCUUGUGUGGCCUUCUCUCCUAGCGCCAAGUACAUUGUCUCUGUGGGCUACCAGCAUGACAUGAUCGUCAACGUGUGGGCCUGGAAGAAAAACAUUGUGGUGGCCUCCAACAAGGUGUCCAGUCGGGUGACAGCAGUGUCCUUCUCUGAGGAUUGCAGCUACUUUGUCACUGCAGGCAACCGACACAUCAAAUUCUGGUAUCUCGAUGACAGCAAGACCUCAAAGGUGAAUGCCACUGUGCCCUUGCUGGGCCGCUCAGGGCUGCUGGGAGAGCUACGGAACAACCUAUUCACUGAUGUGGCCUGUGGCAGAGGAAAAAAGGCGGACAGUACCUUCUGCAUCACGUCCUCAGGGCUGCUGUGCGAGUUCAGUGAUCGAAGGCUUUUGGACAAGUGGGUGGAGCUGAGGAACAUAGACAGCUUCACAACCACAGUGGCCCACUGCAUCUCUGUGAGCCAAGACUACAUCUUCUGUGGCUGUGCUGAUGGCACCGUGCGCCUUUUCAACCCCUCUAACCUGCACUUCCUUAGCACCUUGCCCCGACCCCAUGCUCUGGGGACAGACAUUGCUAGCGUCACCGAGGCCAGUCGCCUCUUCUCUGGAGUGGCGAAUGCCAGGUAUCCAGACACCAUUGCCUUGACCUUUGAUCCUACUAAUCAGUGGCUGUCUUGUGUGUACAACGAUCAUAGCAUUUAUGUUUGGGAUGUGAGGGACCCCAAGAAAGUGGGCAAGGUGUACUCGGCUCUGUAUCAUUCUUCCUGCGUCUGGAGUGUGGAGGUCUACCCCGAGGUGAAGGAUAGUAACCAGGCCUGCCUGCCCCCCAGUUCCUUUAUUACCUGCUCCUCAGACAACACCAUCCGCCUGUGGAACACAGAGAGCUCCGGGGUGCAUGGCUCCACCCUCCACCGAAACAUCCUCAGCAGUGACCUCAUUAAAAUCAUCUAUGUGGAUGGGAACACCCAGGCCCUGCUGGACACAGAGCUGCCUGGAGGAGACAAAGCUGAUGCAUCCCUGUUGGAUCCCCGCGUGGGCAUCCGCUCGGUGUGUGUCAGCCCCAAUGGACAGCAUCUAGCAUCAGGGGACCGUAUGGGCACACUUAGGGUGCACGAACUUCAGUCCCUGAGUGAGAUGCUGAAGGUGGAGGCCCAUGACUCUGAGAUUCUGUGCCUGGAGUAUUCUAAGCCAGACACAGGUCUGAAACUGCUAGCAUCGGCGAGCCGGGACCGGCUGAUCCAUGUGCUGGAUGCCGGGCGGGAGUACAGCCUACAGCAGACGCUGGACGAACACUCAUCCUCCAUCACUGCUGUUAAGUUUGCAGCCAGUGAUGGGCAAGUCCGCAUGAUCAGCUGUGGAGCAGACAAGAGCAUCUACUUCCGCACUGCGCAGAAGUCUGGAGAUGGAGUGCAGUUCACACGGACACACCACGUGGUGCGGAAGACGACCCUCUAUGACAUGGAUGUGGAGCCCAGCUGGAAGUACACGGCUAUCGGCUGCCAGGACCGAAAUAUUCGGAUAUUUAACAUCAGCAGUGGAAAGCAGAAGAAGCUGUUUAAAGGGUCACAGGGUGAGGACGGCACACUCAUUAAGGUGCAGACAGACCCCUCAGGGAUCUACAUUGCCACCAGCUGUUCUGACAAGAAUCUCUCCAUUUUUGACUUCUCCUCAGGCGAGUGCGUGGCCACCAUGUUUGGCCACUCAGAGAUUGUCACUGGCAUGAAAUUUAGUAAUGAUUGUAAACAUCUCAUCUCUGUGUCUGGGGACAGCUGCAUAUUUGUGUGGCGCCUGAGCUCUGAGAUGACCAUCAGCAUGAGGCAGCGUCUGGCCGAGUUGCGCCAGCGUCAGCGGGGCGGCAAGCAGCAAGGACCAUCCUCUCCCCAAAGGGCUUCUGGACCCAACCGGCACCAGGCCCCAUCAAUGCUGUCUCCUGGACCGGCUCUCUCAUCAGACAGUGACAAGGAGGGAGAAGAUGAGGGGACUGAAGAAGAACUUCCAGCACUGCCCGUCCUUGCCAAGAGUACCAAGAAGGCACUGGCCUCGGUCCCCAGCCCAGCUUUGCCCCGAAGCCUGUCCCACUGGGAGAUGAGUCGGGCACAGGAGUCCGUGGGGUUCCUGGACCCAGCUCCUGCAGCCAACCCAGGACCCAGAAGAAGAGGGCGCUGGGUUCAGCCAGGUGUGGAACUGAGCGUUAGAUCCAUGCUGGAUCUGCGGCAGCUGGAAACACUGGCCCCAAGCCUGCAGGACCCUAGCCAGGACUCGCUGGCCAUCAUCCCAUCUGGUCCCAGGAAGCAUGGGCAGGAGGCCCUUGAGACUUCACUCACUAGCCAGAAUGAAAAGCCCCCUCGGCCUCAGGCUUCCCAACCUUGUUCCUAUCCCCAUAUUAUCCGAUUAUUGUCACAAGAGGAAGGGGUCUUUGCCCAAGAUCUGGAACCUGCACCCAUUGAAGAUGGUAUUGUCUACCCGGAGCCGAGUGACAACCCCACCAUGGAUACCAGUGAGUUCCAAGUGCAGGCUCCAGCCCGGGGAACUCUGGGAAGAGUGUACCCAGGCAGCAGGAGCUCAGAAAAGCACAGCCCUGACAGUGCCUGCUCUGUGGAUUACAGCAGCAGCUGCCUUUCCAGCCCGGAGCACCCCACUGAAGACUCUGAGAGCACGGAGCCCCUCAGUGUGGAUGGCAUCUCCUCAGACCUUGAAGAGCCAGCUGAGGGUGAUGAAGAAGAGGAAGAAGAGGAGGGAGGCAUGGGCCCCUAUGGGCUACAGGAGGGCAGCCCCCAGACUCCAGACCAGGAGCAGUUUCUAAAACAGCACUUUGAGACUCUGGCCAGUGGAGCUGCUCCAGGGGCCCCAGUGCAGGUCCCAGAGAGGUCAGAGUCUCGGAGUAUCUCUUCACGAUUCCUGUUGCAAGUACAGACCCGCCCACUCAGGGAACCAUCCCCAUCCUCCUCAAGCCUGGCACUGAUGUCGAGACCAGCCCAGGUGCCACAGGCAUCUGGUGAGCAGCCGAGAGGCAAUGGUGCCAAUCCCCCUGGAGCACCCCCGGAGGUGGAACCGUCCUCUGGCAACCCCAGCCCCCAGCAGGCAGCCUCUGUGCUGUUGCCACGAUGCCGUCUCAACCCUGACAGCAGCUGGGCUCCCAAGAGAGUGGCCACAGCCAGCCCCUUUUCUGGACUCCAGAAGGCCCAGUCUGUGCACAGUCUGGUGCCACAGGAAAGACAUGAGGCCAGUCUGCAGGCCCCUUCACCAGGCGCACUGCUGUCUCGGGAGAUCGAAGCUCAGGAUGGUCUGGGCUCCCUGCCCCCAGCUGAUGGCCGUCCGUCUCGGCCUCACUCCUAUCAGAACCCCACCACCAGUUCCAUGGCCAAGAUAUCCCGCAGUAUCUCUGUUGGGGAGAACCUGGGCCUGGUGGCUGAACCUCAAGCUCAUGCCCCCAUCCGAGUCUCACCACUCAGCAAGCUGGCCCUGCCCAGCCGGGCUCACCUGGUCCUGGACAUCCCCAAACCACUGCCUGACCGUCCUACCCUGGCUGCAUUCUCUCCUGUCACCAAAGGCCGGGCCCCUGGCGAGGCAGAAAAGCCUGGCUUCCCGGUGGGCCUAGGAAAAGCUCACAGUACAACUGAGAGAUGGGCCUGUUUGGGGGAGGGCACCACUCCCAAGCCUAGGACAGAGUGCCAGGCUCAUCCUGGGCCCAGCAGCCCCUGUGCCCAGCAACUGCCAGUCAGCAGCCUCUUCCAAGGCCCUGAAAACUUGCAGCCCCCACCCCCUGAGAAGACUCCCAACCCCAUGGAAUGCACCAAGCCAGGGGCAGCCCUGAGCCAGGACUCAGAGCCAGCGGUGAGCCUGGAGCAGUGUGAGCAGCUGGUGGCAGAGCUCCGCGGCAGCGUGCGCCAGGCAGUGCGGCUCUACCACUCGGUGGCUGGCUGCAAGAUGCCCUCAGCAGAGCAAAGUCGGAUUGCCCAGCUCCUCAGAGACACCUUCUCUUCAGUGCGACAGGAGCUGGAAGCUGUGGCUGGGGCAGUGCUGUCCAGCCCAGGCAGCAGCCCUGGGGCUGUGGGAGCCGAGCAGACACAGGCCCUGCUGGAGCAAUACUCAGAACUGUUGCUUCGAGCCGUGGAACGGCGUAUGGAACGCAAACUCUGAGUUCUGGAAGCCUGUCCCAAGUGAAUGAAUGCUCCAGCGAUUCCAAACUGCAGCCCCUCUGCCCCUCACCAAAACCUGCGGGGCUGCUUGGAGUGGAAAGCAGGGAGCAGUGUUCAGAGGCAAAGCAGCCUUCCCAGCCGCUCCUCGUGGGGGGCCUGUAUUUAUUAAUUUAUUUCCCUGACUGUUGCCUCACUUCCUUGGAACUCCUGCCUCCACAGCCCCUCCAGUGGCAGGGACAGGUCUUGGGUCUUUGUCAUCUUGGUGCUGUGAGAGGUAGGAGGGCAGCCUGCCCCAUCUAGGAAUCUGGGAAGGGCUGGCCCUCUCUUAGAAGCCAUUUGAAAUUACUGCAGGGAUUAGCUCCCUGUGGUGGAGCAUACACAGGGUACUCUGGGGUCGAGGUGAGAGGUGAUGUGGUAUUCAGUGCCCGUCAGCCAACUGUGGGCCUUCACCUCUACCUGCACUUCCCCUCUCACACCAGCUGCACUCCCGUGGCUGCCAGAGCAGGGUGGUUUUCCCCAAUACCUGGAGCUCAGAAAGGCAGAGCCAUCUGGCCCUCCAGGGUGUCCCCAGCCAUCAGGAGACUUGAGUUGGUAUUUGGACCUGAGCCCGCACAUUCCACUCCCAUUCUCCCUCCAAGAGGGGCCCAGCAUUGUAUUUCCCUGUGACCCCUUACUCUCCUGGCCAGAACUUGAGCCAGCUGUGGGAUGUUGCUGCAGGACAGUAAGCCCUCACCUGGGCAAACAUGAAGCUCUGGCCUCCUUUCCUCAGCCCCUUGUUCUUCCCUGUCCUCCACCCUGGACCCCAGCCGGCUGCUGGAGCCCAGAGGCCACCUUCUCCCUGCAUCCUGAAUGAUGCUUAGUCAGAAGCCUGUGUUGGAACAUCCCUCGUUUACGGGGCGCUGGCCUACCUCCUGAGGACCUCAGCCACAGAUGAGAUCACACGCAUGCACGUGCACACAUGUACACACACACACCUACCUGCACAGCACGCUGUUGAGUGUUGGUUGCUAGAGUAUCUGGCUGGCUGCUGUGUGCCUGGUUUCCUCACAUCCUGCCUCAGCUUCACCACCCUGGCUUAUGUGGAACACCUAUCAGGGAGCAGAAAAGGGGUGCAGUACACUAAGUGAACCCAGAUUCUGGAUUCUUGGUGUCCACAGCCUAGCUGAUACGAGAUAGCCCAUAGGACACCUGGUUUAGGUAGAAGGAGCCUCCUCAAAGGCAGUGCUGGGCACCCACGGGUGUGCUGGAUACUGGAGUUUGAGAGGAGGGAGGUGCUGGGGCCAAAGGAGACACUAGAAAAGUGGUAGAUGGGACAGGUAAGUGGCAGAGGUGAGGGGAUAAGUUAGAAUGUAAAAGGGCAGUAAUUAGGGGUGAGGGAAAGGAGAUAGGGGACCCUAGGAGGUAGAGUGGGACCAUGUCGUGAGGCAGUUGAAGAGUUGAGGAAAGGUUUUUCUGGGCCCUACUGCUCCCCUCUGCUGCAGGUAAGUCAGAGCAGCUUUACCACAGCUUCAGGCCACGAGAGCCCCUUCACCCGCCCUGCUGCGCCAUAGGCAGAGGCUUAUAAAGAAAUGGGUUCUGGGCCAGGUGUGGUGGCUCAAGCCUGUAAUCCCAGCACUUUGGGAGGCCGAGGCGGGUGGAUCACCUGAGGUUAGGAGUUCGAGAUCAGCCUGGCCAACAUGGUGAAACCCUGUCUACUAAAAAUAAAAAAAUUAGCUGGGCGUGGUGGUGGGCGCCUGUAAUCCCAGCUACUCGGGAGGUUUAGGCAGGAGAAUCGCUUGAACCCUGGAGGUGGAGGUGGAGGUUGCAGUGAGCCGAGAUCGCGCCAUUGCACUCCAACCUAGGUGACAAAGCUACACGCCAUCUCAAAAAAAAAAAAGAAAAAGGGUUACAAAAGGUUCCCAGCUCCGGGGCAUCAGCCUGAGUGCGCUUGAGCUGCUCCAAACCUGGCCCUUCCCCACUCCUCUAGCAUCGCCACCCGCAUGGCCCUGGAACUCCCGCGGCGGCGGGGGCGGGCCCGUGCCUGCUGUGCCCCGACUUCCCACACCAGCCGCGCCCACCGCAGGUGGGACUCAGGUUCGCCCUCUGGGCCAGGUCCUUCACGAGGAGGGAGCUACCCUUCGCCAGAAGUUUGUGAGAAUGUGGCCGCCCUUUUCCUGCCCUCUGCCCCAUGUGGGUGGGGGGCCUCGUGGCCCGGCCGGCGCCCCGUCCCCUUCUGCAUGUCUGAGGCCACCGGCAACCGCCGCCCCACUCCAGAUUUGCCCCCGCCUUGUUUUGAAAGCCCCUUAUUUAUAACUUUUAUACUUUGUGCAGGUCGCGGCGCUUCCUGCCUCAUCCUCGGCUGCAUGGGGCGGGGGCGCUGUUUUUAACGUGCCCGUUUGUACUGAUGUAUGAACUUGUCAAUAAACACAAUUGUUUGUUAA